AUCUCUCUCGGGUGGAGUCUUCUGACAGCUGGUGCGCCUGCCCGGGAACAUCCUCCUGGACUCAAUCAUGGCUUGUGGUCUGGUCGCCAGCAACCUGAAUCUCAAACCUGGAGAGUGCCUUCGAGUGCGAGGCGAGGUGGCUCCUGACGCUAAGAGCUUCGUGCUGAACCUGGGCAAAGACAGCAACAACCUGUGCCUGCACUUCAACCCUCGCUUCAACGCCCACGGCGACGCCAACACCAUCGUGUGCAACAGCAAGGACGGCGGGGCCUGGGGGACCGAGCAGCGGGAGGCUGUCUUUCCCUUCCAGCCUGGAAGUGUUGCAGAGGUGUGCAUCACCUUCGACCAGGCCAACCUGACCGUCAAGCUGCCAGAUGGAUACGAAUUCAAGUUCCCCAACCGCCUCAACCUGGAGGCCAUCAACUACAUGGCAGCUGACGGUGACUUCAAGAUCAAAUGUGUGGCCUUUGACUGAAAUCAGCCAGCCCAUGGCCCCCAAUAAAGGCAGCUGCCUCUGCUCCCUCUGAA